UUUGGCGGGCAGCAGAGGUCAAACCCCAGAGCAGAGGAGAUGAGAGGCCCGGCCAGUUCCGAGGCCUUCCCAGAGGAAACCUCGCCCACAGAUCUGCAGGAAGUUGAACUAAUGAGUUGAGAAAGCUUCGGAGAUGGACAACGCUCAGCCCUGUCCUCAAAAAUUUAUGGUCAAGUGAGGACAGAGGAACAUGUACAACCGUCUUCUACAUACUACUCAUUCAACACUCACGACAACCCUGUGAGACAGGCACUGCUUAGGGAUCGGCGAUUCCAAAGUGAACAAACAGAUCCCCAGAAGCUGCCCCCGUGGAGCUGACAUCCUAGUGUGGAGACAUAGACGAUAAACGAAGAAAGCAAAGUUAGUAAAAUACAGAAUAUGUCAGGUGGAGAUGAGUACGAAGAAGCAUAAAACCAAGAGGGGCACCGUGAGUCCCAGUGGUAUGCAAAUGGUGGUUUUCAAUCCUGGGGUCAGAGAGGACCACAGCAAGAAACUGACACGUGAACAAAAGUCUGGAGGAGGUGAUGGAUGAGAAAACAGAGGCAGAGAGAUGGGGCAGGACCUGUUCCAGGUCGUCCUGCCCCACAUCGAUCUCAAGAGGCAGAGACUUUCACAUGCCCAUUUCACAGAUGAGAGAACUGAGGACCAUGAGCAAGAGGCUUUCCAGCAUCUCGCAGAGGCUGAACUGGGAUCAGGCAGGAAACACACGCUAUGAGGAACUACCCACAUGCCCACAUCAGGCAGGAGGACCCCGGCGGGUGCAAGGGUGGAAGUCGUCUCUUCAUGGCUGCACCCUUGGCCAGUGCCAGUCCAGCAGCCUCUUUCAAAGAAGCUUUUAUAGGCAGAUAGUUUGUCAGCCCAGCUCGAAAUGUGAACAAGGUAGCAGCCGAGCCCCCACCCAUCCGGCUGCACUCCCCUGCAUGUCCAGCCCCGAGCCCUGUGUCAAGCACACCUCCUUGGGAGGAGACCGCCCCAGCCUGCAAGGAAGUGCUCAUUAUGGAGAGUGGAGAGUGACAGGCCACUCCCGGCCACGUCUCCAAGCAAGCCGGUGCCCCCUCCUCCUGCUGCCACCGCCCACUGAGCUGCCUGGGCUGCAGACGCCCUGGUUGGAGCGUCUGGGGCCAGAUGUUAUAGGGCAAGCUAAAAAUAACCGGGCAGGCCAGCCACCAUCGAGGAAGGGGCAUGUGCUGGACGCGGACACAUGA